AUUGUGCCCUACCAGAGAGGACAGAUGGGCACCGCCUCCAGUGGCAAUGCUAAUUCACCCAAGAGGCCUUCCCAGCUCUUCUCACAGAAGGAAGAUAAACUCCACAUAUUUCUGAGCGCAGCCGCCGCCGCCGCCGCCGCCGCGUCCUCUCAGCCUUGCGCUCCGCCCGCUGCCUCUGCCGCCGCAGCGCAGAGCCGGGCGCACCGGCCCCGCAGCCUGCCCACUCUUCGGGCCGCGUGCCGGCUGCAGCCGGCAUGGGGGGUUGCUGAGAGCGAGCACUCCUUUCCUCUGGCACCUCCCCCGGCUACUGGCCACUGGACUCUGGCCAGCGAGGCUCGGCCCCUCUGGCCCCCAGUCUGGCGCCUGGCACGGCCCUCUACUCUGCUCCUCCAGCUCUGAGCAUCGUGUCUUCGCCGCCCCCCCCGCCCGCGCCUGGGAUACCUGGGUCCCCCGGCGACCCCUAGGAGAGGGGCGGGGGGGGGCAUGAAGCCGCUGGAGAAAUUUCUGAAGAAGCAGACGUCGCAGCUGGCGGGCCGAACGGUGGCGGGAGGUCCCGGCGGGGGUCUGGGGAGCUGCGGUGGGCCUGGAGGGGGUGGGGGACCCGGCGGGGGCGGCGGUCCAGCCGGGGGACAGCGGUCGUUGCAGCGGCGUCAGAGCGUGUCUCGCCUGCUGCUCCCCGCUUUCCUCCGGGAGCCCCCCGCCGAGCCGGGGCUGGAGCCGCCCCCUGAGGAGGAAGGAGGAGAGCCGGCGGGGGUCGCGGAGGAGCCGGGCAGCGGGGGGCCCUGCUGGCUGCAGCUGGAGGAGGUGCCGGGGCCCGGGCCUCUCGGGGGAGGGGGGCCCCUGCGCUCCCCUUCCUCCUACUCAUCUGACGAGCUGUCCCCAGGCGAGCCCUUGACUUCGCCGCCCUGGGCCCCUCUGGGCGCCCCCGAGCGGCCCGAGCAUCUUCUGAACCGGGUUCUGGAGCGGCUUGCUGGAGGGGCUACCAGGGACAGCGCCGCCUCAGAUAUCCUGCUGGAUGACAUUGUCCUUACCCAUUCUCUCUUCCUCCCGACGGAGAAAUUUCUGCAGGAGCUACACCAGUACUUUGUUCGGGCAGGAGGCAUGGAGGGCCCUGAAGGGCUGGGCCGGAAGCAAGCCUGUCUAGCCAUGCUUCUCCAUUUCUUGGACACCUACCAGGGGCUGCUUCAAGAGGAAGAGGGGGCCGGCCACAUCAUCAAGGAUCUAUACCUGCUAAUUAUGAAGGACGAGUCCCUUUACCAGGGCCUCCGAGAGGACACUCUGAGGCUGCACCAGCUGGUGGAGACGGUGGAACUAAAGAUUCCAGAGGAGAACCAGCCACCCAGCAAGCAGGUGAAGCCACUCUUCCGCCACUUCCGCCGGAUAGACUCCUGUCUGCAGACCCGGGUGGCCUUCCGGGGCUCUGAUGAGAUCUUCUGCCGUGUAUACAUGCCUGACCACUCUUAUGUGACCAUACGCAGCCGCCUUUCAGCAUCUGUGCAGGACAUUCUGGGCUCUGUGACGGAGAAACUUCAAUAUUCAGAGGAGCCCGCGGGGCGUGAGGAUUCCCUCAUCCUGGUAGCUGUGUCCUCCUCUGGAGAGAAGGUCCUUCUCCAGCCCACUGAGGACUGUGUUUUCACCGCACUGGGCAUCAACAGCCACCUGUUUGCCUGUACUCGGGACAGCUAUGAGGCUCUGGUGCCCCUCCCCGAGGAGAUCCAGGUCUCCCCUGGAGACACAGAGAUCCACCGAGUGGAGCCUGAGGACGUUGCCAACCACCUAACUGCCUUCCACUGGGAGCUGUUCCGAUGUGUGCAUGAGCUGGAGUUCGUGGACUACGUGUUCCACGGGGAGCGCGGCCGCCGGGAGACGGCCAACUUGGAGCUGCUGCUGCAGCGCUGCAGCGAGGUCACGCACUGGGUGGCCACCGAAGUGCUGCUCUGCGAGGCCCCGGGCAAGCGCGCGCAGCUGCUCAAGAAGUUCAUCAAGAUCGCGGCCCUCUGCAAGCAGAACCAGGACCUGCUGUCUUUCUACGCCGUGGUCAUGGGGCUGGACAACGCCGCUGUCAGCCGCCUUCGACUCACCUGGGAGAAGCUGCCAGGGAAAUUCAAGAACUUGUUUCGCAAAUUUGAGAACCUGACGGACCCCUGCAGGAACCACAAAAGCUACCGAGAAGUGAUCUCCAAAAUGAAGCCCCCUGUGAUUCCCUUCGUGCCUCUGAUCCUCAAAGACCUGACUUUCCUGCACGAAGGGAGUAAGACCCUUGUAGAUGGUUUGGUGAACAUCGAGAAGCUGCAUUCAGUGGCCGAAAAAGUGAGGACAAUCCGCAAAUACCGGAGCCGGCCCCUUUGCCUGGACAUGGAGGCAUCCCCCAAUCACCUGCAGACCAAGGCCUAUGUGCGCCAGUUUCAGGUCAUCGACAACCAGAACCUCCUCUUCGAGCUCUCCUACAAGCUGGAGGCAAACAGUCAGUGAGAGUGGAGGCUCCAGUCAGACCCGCCAGAUCCUUGGGCACCUGGCACUCAAGCACUUUGCACGAUGUCUCAACCAACAUCUGACAUCUUUCCCGUGGAGCAACUUCCUGCUCCACGGGAAAGAGGUCGAUGGAUUUACCCCUGGACCCAUAAGUCUGUUCAUCCUGCUGAAGUCCCCUCCCCAUUGCUCCUUCAAGCCAAAACUACACUUUGCUGGUUCCUGUCCCCUCUGAGAAAGGGGAUAGAAAGCUCCUUCCUCUAUGUCCUCCCAUCGAGAUCUGUUCUGGGGAUGGAGCUUCCAACUUCCUCUUGCAGCAGGAAAGAAUGCUGCUCACCCUUCUGUCUUGCAGAGUGGGAUUGUGGGAGGGAUUGGCAGCCUUCUUCUCCACCACCUGUCCAGCUUCUUCCUGGUCAGGGCUGGGACCCCCAGGAAUAUUAUGUUGCCGUGUGUGUGUGUGUGUGUGUGUGUGUGUGUGUGUGUGUGUGUGUGUGUGUGUGUGUGUCUUCUUUUAGGGAGCAGGAGUGCAUCUGGUAAUUGAGGGUGGAUGUUGUGUGUGCUGGGGAGGGGUCCUUCUGUUUGGUGCUACCCUUGUCUACUCUGCCCCUGGAUGGUGCGGGGUGCUUUCUCCACCCCCACACUCCCUGCUCAGCUCCUCGUGCUGCCCUGCAUGCCCAGGCUUGUGAGCCAAGCUGCUUUUUGGGGCAGGGAGUAGCAGCAGGUGGGAGGGGUUACCCAUCAGCCCUUGCAAGUCCCCCACUCAGGCCUCUGGAAGGUCCAGGGAUGGGCUCUGAUGAGAGGGUAAAAGAUGCUCAGGGAAACACAGGCCUCAGCUGCCUAGAGGACCCUCCCCCUGCCUUGCAGUGGGCUCGGGUAGAGCAGUAUCAGGAGCUAGGGUUGUCUGCUGCCCACACUCCUGCUUUUUGGGAUAUCUAACUGCUAAGGAGGGAGUUGACAUCCCCCUUCUGGCUCAUGUGUCUGACACCAACAACAUGGUCUCUGUCCCUCUCUCUUUGACUCUCCCUUUGUCCUCCCCAUAGAGCUGGGGUGGGGUGGAUCCCUAUACCUGGGGCAGGCAGCCCCAAAGUGGGGGAGGGGGAUGGCAGAGACUGUAAAGGCGCCACUGGACUCUGGCAAGGCCUUUAUUACCUUUACUCCCCUCCCUCUCCCAUCACCAGCCUCAAGGCCUGAGGGGUGCAGGGGCUCCUGGCAGCUACUGGGUGAGGUUUCCUGGCACAGACUCACCCUUCUUUCUGGCACCACCUCUUUCCCUUUUGAAGAGACAGCAACAGCCGUAGCAAAAGCAGCUGCUGCUCCUGCUAUGAGGGUGUAUAUAUUUUUUACCCAAAGCUCUGGAAUUGUACAUUUAUUUUUUAAAACUCAAAGAGGGAAAGAGCCUUGUAUCAUAUGUGAACAUUGUAUCAUAGGUAAUGUUGUACAGACCCUUUUAUACAGUGAUCUGUCUUGUUCCUGCAGCAAAAAUCCUCUAUGGACAUAGGAGGUGCUGUGUCCCAUGCCCUCUUGCCCUGACAGUGUCCCAUGGGCCCCCUUCUGCUCCCUGCCCCCUCCCUGCUACUGCUGAUGCACUCUCCUCUCCCUGCAGCCCCUGGCUUCCCAGCCUUCCUCCUGACCCCUUCCAACAGCCUUGGAACUCCAGCUGCCACCACCCUCUGGGUCGGACACUGGGACCCACUGGCCCAGUCUUGGCUGCUGCUUACCCCUAGCCUUGAUGCCUGCCCAGGGACCCCCAGCCCCCUCCCGUUGCCCUGCAGCUUUAACAGAGUGAACCAUGUGUAUUGUACAGGCGCGGUUGUCAUUGCAGAAACCGCUGGGUGGAGAAGAAGCCGAUAAAGUCUAUGAAUCAA